CUCCUCCUCGCCCGCGAAGCCAGGGCACCGGCGCAGCGAGAUUCCAGCCCCAGCCCCCUCGGGCGGGCGCCCUGGGGUGUGGAAGGCGCGGGGCUCCCUGUGGCAUCGCCCAAGUAGGGAUGGGGUCGGGCGCCCGCGGCCCCGCCGCGCAGUGCGCUCCUGGCCGACUUCAGUCCGUCUCGCGGCUUCUUCCGGGUUUAUCCCGCGCAGCAGCUGCCGCCUCGGGACACGCUCAUUCCCACGGCCACCGGCAAGCCACUCCUGGCGACUCCCCGGGACCUGAGGAGCCGCGGCGCGGAGGUGACCCUCCCCGGCCUGCGCCUCCCUUCUUCCUCCUCCCCAGCUGGGCGCGUGGUCGCGUCGCCCGGGGACUCUGGUGAUGCCCGAGAAAUGGGCUGGGGGUGCCGGGUGCCAGGAUGGGGUGGGGCGGCCCUAGGCCGGCCUGACUUCGGGACCGGGCUGCGGGCGAGGGUCUCGGGGCCCGGCUCGGCCGGCUUCCGGGCCGAGAAAGAAGGGCAGAGGAAGCGGUCAGGGUCCCCUCCGGCCCCGGCCUCCCUCCCGGAGUAUAAGCCCUUGGAGGCCAGGUUUUGGGUUGCUGCCGCCCAGCUCUUUCGGUCUCCACUUCUCCCCACGGACGUUUACAGCUGCUCGCUUUAUUUCUCCCUCCAUUCCCCCGUGGAGCCCCCUCGGCAGCGGAGGGGUCGCGUGCUUCUCCUCUCCCGCCUGCGCCUCCCCCCUUCCCACCCGACAGCCCAGGAGGAGCUGCGGGCGCGGCCCUGGGACGGCCGGAGCCUGGGGCUUCUGCUCGCUCGCGCCCUCCCAGGCGUUGCCGCGGGUCCGAGCCCCCGCAGAGGUGGGCAUAGCCCCGGGGCCGCAGAAAACGAAGGCAGCUGGGCAGGGAUGCUCAAUUUCCCGAGCCCCACUUUCCUUUCACAGCCCACUGGGAUGUGUAGUUCUUCCGCCCGCAGGCCUGCGCCGAGGAGAAGCACGACUCGGGGCCUUAGAAACUACAAGUCCCUGCAUCCCCCGCGACAAGGGCAGGAGAGGCGUGGUGCUGGGCGUUCUGGGGCUAGGUGGUGGGAGAUGGGAACCAACAAAGGGGGUUGUGGGGAACGGUGCCUUCUCUGUACUGGGCAGUUUGCACGUUACACAUGUUCUUUGUCUAAUCUUCGCCGGAACCCGGUGAGGCAUUAUUGUAUCCAGCUUAGAGAAAGCUUAACUACUGGCCAAACAUCACAAAGCUCCCAAGUAGUAGAGAUGGCAUCGAACCCAGAGCCCUAAGUAUGUCCCUUACAAAGCGUGCCUCAGUGAGGAGUGUCGAAGGGGGAUGAGAUUGGCUUAUCCAAGAGGGCCAGUUGGGAGGAGCUGUGGUAAGGAAAAAGUGAUGGGAAUAGCAAUUAGAGUAUGACAUGCAAUUACAAGGAGUUUUGAAUACAAGUGAAAUUUACAGGGGUCCAUUCCAAAGCCGGUUAGAGUCUAGGGAGAAUGGAUCUUAAGCACACGAUAAUAAUUGGGUUUUAAUUAUUUUAGAUAUUGUAUGAGAGACAAGCAUAUUACAGGGACAAUUAAGUAUUUGUGGCUGGACUAGUUUUAAAAAACCAACUGGAAAGCUUCAUACAUUUCAAGUGAAAGCUCUCAUAUGCUUUCCUGUCCUUUAGCUAAUGAGAUCAACGGGGUAUUAUUCUUAUUCUGUUUAUUGCAAGCACCUUUUCUGUGGGUGUCCAAUUAAUAUAAUAGAUCCAUUGAUUUGAUGGCAUUAAAAAAGACUCCCACUCUUA